AGGGCCGGAAGCACCGGGGCGAGCGUCUAAUCCCUAAUACCCAAUUUUGGUGGCGUGCACCUGGCAAACUGAUGAUUGUGUGGGACGUCUAAUCUCUAGUCGCUCACCCCUCUACUUUACCACAGAGCUAGAAAUCGAUUUGAGGAAAUCUGGUAUCAAUGAGCGGGCGGGGAGACAACCCCACCCCUAAUUUCCCUGUUUACGGAAGUUCUUUCCCGGCCUCCUCAGACUGGUGUCGGCUUCCUUUUUCUCCACACUUCUAGCUACCUUGUUUUUAUCGUUUUCGGCACCUGCCCUUCCCCAGCGCCCCCACCACCCCGAGCACUAUGUAUGAUCGGGCUCCCCGCCUGCUCAAAUUGGCUGAAGGUGGCAGCACUGAGGCCCAUGUGGGUCCUGGAUCCUACCAGGUACCUUUCCUGAAGCAGCAGGCGACAGGUAGUAAUGCACCAUUUCUUUCUUUGACUGCCAGAGAAAGUACUUUUACCAUUGCCUCUAGCAUUGAGAAAGCUGUUCCAGGUCCAGGACACUAUAAUGUUUCAGAAGCACAGUGUAACAUAAAAGGAGGCCAUAGUCUACAAAACCGGGAGAAACGUUUUAAGAAGUUUAUUUCAGAUAAUCCAGGACCAGCAAGCUAUGAUCAGUUUUAUCCUAGAACACAAGAUAUCAUGAACAGAAAAGUAUUAGAGACCAGAGAGCAUCUUCAGUCAAAAAUUUCAAGAUCACCUACACUUACCAGAAGUGUUGAUGUUCCUUCAAUUCCUUCUUGUGGAAAGUCAUAUGGUUAUCAUAUUAAUGAUGAUGGCAGUAUUAUAAAAUGUUUUCCACCUGCUUGUGACAGUACACUUGGUCCAGCAUACUACAAACCUCAAUUUGAUGUUUCCAAUGCAACUUUGAAAUACAAAGGUAUACAUUUUGGCAACUCUUCAGGAAGACAAGAGUUACCUAAAAAGUCAGGUCCUGGUCCAGGACAGUAUGAUAUAGUCCAGAAAAAGACAUCAUAUUAUGAAAAUGUUAACAUCAAGAGAGAUCAACAACAAAAUUAUUGUUCAUUUAUCCCACGACUAUAUGAAAUAAUAGUAUUGCAGGAGAAAAAAAAGGGAGUACCAGGGCCUGGAAAAUAUGACAUUAAAAGUCAAUUUCAGAAGAUAGAAAGUAUGACACCAAAUGCAAAUGAUGCAUCUCCUGCUUUUCUUUCUCAAUCCCAGAGAUUUUUACCUAUGAAAUCAAUCACCCCGGCUCCUGGCACAUAUAAUGAACCUCGAACUGCUCUCAAGUCUUUGAAGAAAACAUCAGGACUGAAAAAUAUUCCAUUUGGUCAAAGUGCUGUUCGAUUCACACAGGACAUCAGGACAGAGGAAAUGCCAGGUCCUGGAUUUUAUAAUGUCUUGAACAAUACUAUAAUUGCCAGUGUUAGAAAUAUCUGCUCAAAGAAACAGAAGAAAAGUGCAUUUGGUUCUUCUGUUCCUCGGACUUUCUUCUCGGUUCAGAAAGAAGCUUGUGCUACCCCUGGACCUGCUGAUUAUCAGGAAUUUUGGCAUUCACAGGGUGUGGGAAUUUCUGAUGAAUUACCUAACUUGACUAACAAAUAUGCUGCUUUCUUGUCAAGAGCCAAAAGAACUAUGAAAGUACCAGAUAUGGUUAUUCCAGCGCCAGGCAGCUAUGAUGUUCACAAAUCAUAUGAGAUGUCCCAAGUUAAGCAUAAAUAUAUGCCACCUCGUAGUUUAGUGGCUAAAAGAAAACAUGCCUCUUUUCUUAGUGCAACUCCUCGGUGCCUAGAAAAAGUGACUGAUGGGCCAGGUCCUGCAGCAUACAAUCCUGUUUUAAGGAAAUCUUGCCCCAUACCCUUAUUUGUGAAAGCAUCAAAGCGCUUUGAAGAGUCCAAAGAGAUUACUCCAGGCCCAGCAACAUAUGAGCUCAGUCCAUUUUUAAGGCAUACUGUUCUGAAGAGAACAUUUAAUGUAACUCUGCCAAAUUCUUUCUUGAUUGAUAGAGAAAUCACUCCUACUCUAGAACAAAAAGCCAAACAAAAACACCAAGGAGGCAAAAUAUAAUCUACUAAAUGAUAUAGUCCAAAGGUAAUAUCUAUUAAUAUAAACGUAAGCUGACAGUUCUCUCACAAAGAAGUACUUCCAUGUUGAUAAUGUCCUCCAUCAGCUGCUCACAGGAACAUAAUUGCUCUUCUAACAUCUAGAGAUAAAAAAUACGUUCUUAUAUAAUAUUUGUUUUUUUCAGAAAAUGUUUCCUGUUACAAAAGCAGUAUGUAUAUAUAUUCAUUGCAUUCUUUCUAAGCGUGUACUACUGAUGCAUCCAUAUAAAAUAUAAUGCUGAAUAAAGACAUCUGAUGAAAA